AGCCUGAACUGUGGGUAGUGAUGUGGUGUGUUUCCUAACACCUCCGGCAGUGAGCCAGGCUUUGAGUGGCUGCGUCUAAACACUUCUUUCCCUGAGGACUGGAAGACAUUAGAAUAAGCUCCAGACAAUUCAAACAUUGAGAUUCCUGGGAACUACCAGAUAGUAGCAUCAGUUCACCAAGAAAUGAAGCUGGUGAGGCAGUGAAAAUCCAGGGCCUAGAAAGCUGGGAAUGCCAUGACGUGGGCACAUUGAAAGACAAGAGGCAGGCAUGAUCAGCCUUGAACUUUAGGAAGAUCCCAGGAAGCUGAUGGAAGACAAGAUGUGGAGUGAAUGUGAAGGUCCAGAAAUGUCCUUGGUGUGUUUGACAGACUUUCAGGCCCAUGCGCGAGAGCAGCUGUCUAAGUCAACUCGGGAUUUUAUUGAAGGUGGAGCAGAUGACAGCAUCACGCGGGAUGACAACAUUGCAGCAUUUAAAAGAAUUCGCCUCCGUCCGCGGUACCUGAGAGAUGUGUCUGAGGUGGACACCAGAACCACAAUCCAAGGGGAGGAGAUCAGUGCCCCUAUUUGUAUCGCACCCACAGGGUUCCACUGCCUUGUCUGGCCUGAUGGGGAAAUGAGCACAGCAAGAGCUGCCCAAGCGGCUGGUAUCUGCUACAUCACCAGCACAUUUGCCAGCUGUAGCCUUGAAGACAUUGUCAUUGCAGCUCCCGAAGGCCUCCGAUGGUUCCAACUCUAUGUGCAUCCAGACCUGCAGCUGAACAAACAGUUGAUCCAGAGGGUAGAAUCCCUAGGUUUCAAAGCUUUGGUAAUAACUUUGGAUACACCUGUAUGUGGCAACAGGCGACAUGACAUUCGAAACCAGUUGAGGAGGAACUUAACACUAACAGAUCUUCAAUCACCUAAAAAGGCAUUUAUCGAACACCUGCUCUGUGCCAGACACUGCGGAUAAAGCAGUUUCAAAAAGCAGAUAUGGUUCCUGCUCCCUAGAGUUUCCAGACAAGCACAAUCAACAUAAGACCAAAUGUUCUCACCCUUGGAGCUGCCCAACUUGUCACCAGAAGUGUUCUGGCCAGAGCUGGAUGCUGAGAAAUAGGAAAGCCACGGAAAAUAUUUUUGCACGAACUGGAGAGUAAACUAAAAAAGUUCAUGUAACAUUUUCUACUUUAUGACACACUCAGAAAAUGCUAAUUUUGGAUGGCAUACAUAGACAAACUGACUCUCCAAAGGGGAUGUUCAUGACCAAAGUGACUGGCCAGACAGUCUAGACAGGCCAGGUUCUACCUUACUGCCUUGAAACUGAGGAAUCAAUAUCUCUGCACACAUAGAGCUCAUUUGUGGAGCACCAGGAUGCUAUAGCACAUUUGUUUGUAAUCUCUGAACUAGGUGACUACAAAGGGGACCUUCCCCAUUAAAAUCCUACAAUUAAAUGGCAAGAAGUGCCUCAGAGAGAGACAGCCAUGAUAAAGUGGGAAUCCCUGGCUAUAGUAGAGAUACUAAAGCCAGCCUUUUCAACCAGUGGGCAACUGUGACACCAAGCCAAGUAACUCAACAGUUCUCAUUAAUCACAGAUUGGCCUUGAGGUGCUCCAAAAUCCUUAUUCAAAUUCCAGAAGCACAUUGAGAUUUAUAAAUGUUUGAUGUACAUGGUGAGCCAAGAGUAAAUAUUGGGUAAUAACUGAUUUAGUAUUGCUUAGUUCUUAUCCUGGGUAUGCCUCAACCGUAACAUAUCACAUUGACCAAUAAAUGCUUUUGCUUAUCCA